AUUUGGAGCAUUUCCUUCCCUGACAGCCGGACCUGGGACUGGGCUGGGGCCCUGGCGGAUGGAGACAUGCUGCCCCUGCUGCUGCUGCCCCUGCUGUGGGGGGGGUCCCUGCAGGAGAAGCCAGUGUACGAGCUGCAAGUGCAGAAGUCGGUGACGGUGCAGGAGGGCCUGUGCGUCCUUGUGCCCUGCUCCUUCUCUUACCCCUGGAGAUCCUGGUAUUCCUCUCCCCCACUCUACGUCUACUGGUUCCGGGACGGGGAGAUCCCAUACUACGCUGAGGUUGUGGCCACAAACAACCCAGACAGAAGAGUGAAGCCAGAGACCCAGGGCCGAUUCCGCCUCCUUGGGGAUGUCCAGAAGAAGAACUGCUCCCUGAGCAUCGGAGAUGCCAGAAUGGAGGACACGGGAAGCUAUUUCUUCCGCGUGGAGAGAGGAAGGGAUGUAAAAUAUAGCUACCAACAGAAUAAGCUGAACUUGGAGGUGACAGCCCUGAUAGAGAAACCCGACAUCCACUUUCUGGAGCCUCUGGAGUCCGGCCGCCCCACAAGGCUGAGCUGCAGCCUUCCAGGAUCCUGUGAAGCGGGACCACCUCUCACAUUCUCCUGGACGGGGAAUGCCCUCAGCCCCCUGGACCCCGAGACCACCCGCUCCUCGGAGCUCACCCUCACCCCCAGGCCCGAGGACCAUGGCACCAACCUCACCUGUCAGAUGAAACGCCAAGGAGCUCAGGUGACCACGGAGAGAACUGUCCAGCUCAAUGUCUCCUAUGCUCCACAGACCAUCACCAUCUUCAGGAACGGCAUAGCCCUAGAGAUCCUGCAAAACACCUCAUACCUUCCGGUCCUGGAGGGCCAGGCUCUGCGGCUGCUCUGUGAUGCUCCCAGCAACCCCCCUGCACACCUGAGCUGGUUCCAGGGCUCCCCUGCCCUGAACGCCACCCCCAUCUCCAAUACCGGGAUCUUGGAGCUUCGUCGAGUAAGGUCUGCAGAAGAAGGAGGCUUCACCUGCCGCGCUCAGCACCCGCUGGGCUUCCUGCAAAUUUUUCUGAAUCUCUCAGUUUACUCCCUCCCACAGUUGCUGGGCCCCUCCUGCUCCUGGGAGGCUGAGGGUCUGCACUGCAGAUGCUCCUUUCGAGCCCGGCCGGCCCCCUCCCUGUGCUGGCGGCUUGAGGAGAAGCCGCUGGAGGGGAACAGCAGCCAGGGCUCAUUCAAGGUCAACUCCAGCUCAGCUGGGCCCUGGGCCAACAGCUCCCUGAUCCUCCACGGGGGGCUCAGCUCCGACCUCAAAGUCAGCUGCAAGGCCUGGAACAUCUAUGGGUCCCAGAGCGGCUCUGUCCUGCUGCUGCAAGGGAGAUCGAACCUCGGGACAGGAGUGGUUCCUGCAGCCCUUGGUGGUGCUGGUGUCAUGGCCCUGCUCUGUAUCUGUCUGUGCCUCAUCUUCUUUUUAAUAGUGAAAGCCCGCAGGAAGCAAGCAGCUGGGAGACCAGAGAAAAUGGAUGAUGAAGACCCCAUUAUGGGUACCAUCACCUCGGGUUCCAGGAAGAAGCCCUGGCCAGACAGCCCCGGAGAUCAAGCAUCUCCUCCUGGGGAUGCCCCUCCCUUGGAAGAACAAAAGGAGCUCCAUUAUGCCUCCCUUAGUUUUUCUGAGAUGAAGUCGAGGGAGCCUAAGGACCAGGAGGCCCCAAGCACCACGGAGUACUCGGAGAUCAAGACAAGCAAGUGAGGAUUUGCCCAGAGUUCAGUCCUGGCUGGAGGAGCCACAGCCUGUCUGGGGGAAAGGACAAGUCAGGGACCACUUGCUGAAGCACGAAGAGCCCUUGUGGCAAUGUUAACAUUAACUGAUGUUUAAGUGCUCCAAGCAGAUGGAAUUAGAGAGGUGGGCUCAAAUCUAGGCCCUGGCACUGUCAUCAAGCAAUUCACUGCAUCCCUCUGUGCCUCAGUUUCCCAUUCUGUAAAUCAGAGAUCAUGCAUGCUACCUCAAAGGUUGUUGUGAACAUUAAAGAAAUCAACACAUGGAAAUCAACCAACAUGGGUCCUGGAACAGGGCGUUGUGCUCAGUGCUUUCUGGUCUCUCUUCCUUGAAUAGAAAGGUCCUGCUGGCAAGUUCUCUCAAGGCUGGGGAUGACCAGGCACAAAAAACAGGGCAGCAAUAUGUUGGUGUCACUCCCCUUCCCAAAACUCUUCGAAGACUCCCUAGGAAAGACCAGCCCCUCAGCCUGGCACUUGGUUCAUGAUGUGGGAUCUUAUAUCCUUGCCAGAGUCAUAUCUUUGCCCACUUUUACCUGCAAUCCUUGCAUCAUAUUCCUUUGGCUCCAGUCCUUCAUUUAUGAGACCCAUAGGAAUCCUUCCAACAGCCAAAGAGUUGAGUCUAACUCUUUCCUGCCCAAACCCAUUCACGGCCCCCUGGCCUUAGACAAUAUAUCACAAGCAUCUCCCCUGACACAUAAAGUCCUUCAUGAUCUCCCUGCUAUCUAUUCAUUUAUACUUUCCUCUUGCCUAACCCUUCCUUAAGCCUUUCAUGCUGGUUCAUACCACACUGUCUUUGCAAUUUGAGAUUCCUCCUCCUGGAAGCCAUGCCUCCUUGCUUUCAUCUGGCUUACACUAUCUUUUCCUCCAAACAUGAGUUAAUGGGUGGUCUUGAGUUGGAAGAGUGGACUGAAGAAAGAACUUAUACUCUCCCUCCUCUAAAAUUGAACUAAUUUAUUUUUUAAAAUGCUAAACCAAAAGCAGCUAAAAAUUCUCCAGUUACUUAUCUAGGGUAUCUCCAAACCCAGAUAAAUGACAAUGUUAGAAACUUCAGCAAGUGGUCAUGAGGAAAUGAGUGGAUAAUUCCAGUGGAGUACUGGGAGGACAUUGAUUCUCAAUAUCUACCACCCAAACUUCAUUUUCAUCACUGUAAAGAAGGUGAAUUGUGACUACUGUUUUGGUUAUGACAGGUUAGAUAAUUUUGAUCAAGCCUUGUGUUGAAAAUAAUAAAAUCUUUUGGGGAAAAAA